GGGCACGCAGGAGACACAGGACAGAGCCCACCACGUCUCAGAGCUGUGGGACGGUGGUGGGUCCGGUCCCCACCCCACCUUGCUGGGGCACAGGUUAGCUUGCCCAUCUCUGGGUUCACGGUCCCUGCCAGGAGUUUGGGUAAUGCCUCACACAGGGACCUUCGGGUCCAAGGGCUGUUGGUGCUUGCCCUGCAGUUCCCUCUCCUGCACUGGGCCUGGUGAAUGACACUAAUUCAGAGACGUACAACACGAUCUGGGCAUCGCCAGCAAAGUCCAGCCAGCGUUUGAUGACAGCCUACCCUCCACAAGCUCAGAGUCUGGUGAGGGAGGCUGUGGCAUGAAUAAGGGCAAAAACAGAGGGCAGGCCAGGUGCAGUGGCUCACGCCUGUAAUCCUAGCACUUUGGGAAGCCCAGGUGGGAAGAUCGCCUGAGCCCAGGAGUUCAAGACCAGCGUGGCCAACAUGGCCAGACACUGUCUCUAUAGAUUGGAAAAAAGACAAAGCAGAGGCCAGGCCCCCAGUUCCCCACCUGUGUCAGCCUACCAGGAGGAGAAAUCACUCGGCGUUCCCUGAACAGAUCAGACCCCGGGUCUUUGCACAAGCUGUGCCCCCGGGCAGCGGCCCUCCCCUGCCUGCAGGAUUCGUGCGUGGAGACUGAUUUGCUGUCGGCCGGGGCUUCACUCUGGGCUUCUUGGAUCCCAUCCCCAGCUGCUCACACUCCACAUCGGUCCACCUACUAUGCUCCCGGCACCCUUAGGGCUGAGGGAGACUGGAGUUGGCCGAGCCCGAUUUGGGACGCGUGCGUCGGGGUUGGUGAGGCUGCGGAUAGCGCUGGAACCGGGCAGGUUCCACGCAGGCGCGGGGGACGACGGCGGGGGCUACACGGUGGAGGUGAGCAUCAAUGACUACCUGGACAUCUACUGCCCGCACUAUGGGGCGCCGCUGCCGCCGGCCGAGCGCAUGGAGCACUACGUGCUGUACAUGGUCAACGGCGAGGGCCACGCCUCCUGCGACCACCGCCAGCGCGGCUUCAAGCGCUGGGAGUGCAACCGGCCCGCGGCGCCCGGGGGGCCGCUCAAGUUCUCGGAGAAGUUCCAGCUCUUCACGCCCUUCUCCCUGGGCUUCGAGUUCCGGCCCGGCCACGAGUAUUACUACAUCUCUGCCACGCCUCCCAAUGCUGUGGACCGGCCCUGCCUGCGACUGAAGGUGUACGUGCGGCCGACCAACGAGACCCUGUACGAGGCUCCUGAGCCCAUCUUCACCAGCAAUAACUCGUGUAGCAGCCCGGGCGGCUGCCGCCUCUUCCUCAGCACCAUCCCCGUGCUCUGGACCCUCCUGGGUUCCUAGUCCCAGCCCCGCAGGACGCCGACCCUGCCUGGACGGCCCCGCCUGGACCGCCUGACCUCGGCCCUCCGGACCCGGCUGCGGCCCCCGCCUCCGAGACCAAAUAGAGACGCUGCUUCUCCCUCGCCUGGUGCCGCCCCCGCCGGGCAGGGGCCAUCCACCCGCCCCAGGACCAGCCCUCAGGGAGGGGAAACGGCCGAGAGCCCCCCCCCGGAGGCCCGAGGGGCCGGGGUGUGGAUGCGGACCGUGGCCAGGCCAUCUCCUCUGGGGCGUCGGAGAACCCGGGAACCUCUUGGCGAUUUUUUUUUUUUUUUUUUUUUUUUUUUUUUUUUUUAGUGUAUUUUUCGUGGUUGGAUCAAAAAGACUUGAGUUUUUAAUUUAAUUUAUUCCCUGCCGUUGUAGCGGGGCGGGGUCCCUGUGCCCUGGCCUGGGGGAGGGGAACGCGGAACAUGGGGUCGGGAACACAGCCGCUCCCCUCUGCUCUGCACCCCACUCGUGGGGGAACACAGCCGCUCCCCUCUGCUCUGCACCCCACUCGUGGGGGAACACAGCCGCUCCCCUCUGCUCUGCACCCCACUCGUGGGGGAACACAGCCGCUCCCCUCUGCUCUGCACCCCACUCGUGGGGGAACACAGCUGCAGCCCACCGCGGACCCCCCUGGUGCUCCAGGUUGGGUGAGUCUGAGCCGGAAGGGGUACGUGGUGGGCGCCCCUCAUUGUGGCUGGGGAGACCUCAUACCCCAUCGCCCACCCCCGUCCUCCUGGUCAUUUCCUCCCAGACACUGUUUUGCCCCAGCGCCCUUCGGAAUCACAGUCCCGCCGUGUCUUAGAAACUGCUUUGGCCGAUGCAAACAGCCCCCUACCCGUCCCCCUCGCCUCACACGGUCCCUCUCCGAGGCCGAGAAGACCUUCUGUUCCUGUAAAUACAGCCAGCAAGUGCAAACUGUGAUUUUAUUUUCCACGUAUUCCUGAGGACGGACUGGACCGUCUAUGUUUUUUCAGCCCUUCAUAGGGGGUCUUUUAUUUUGGUGGGGGGGUGGGGUGGACUUUUAGAGUAGAAGCUGCACUUGGCAAUAAGCUCGUGUCGUCUGUCAGAGCCCCUCUCUCAACUCUGUGACCUGAUAAUGUUUCUAAGAAAAAGAAAAAAAGGACAAAAGGGAGGGAACCACUACCAAAAAAAAAAAAAGAAACUCCUCCCCGAAGACACUUUAAUGAAGGAAACAACACAUUUAUACGGAUUUCAUAUUUCUACCCGCCUUUCCUGACUCUGUGUUUUAUAUAUAUUAUAUAUAAAUAUAUAUUGUGUACGGCCGCCGGCCGGCGGCUCGAGGCACGCCCGGUGGUGGGGGGUGGGCAGAGGGCUUUUGUAGGGGGUCGGCGGGGCGGGCCGCGUUGCCAGGCCUGGAGCUGGCGACCGGGCCUCCCUCUUCCCGUCACAAUCAACUUUGGAUUCUGUAUUUUUUUAUAAUAAAAUGAGCAUAAACCUCAAA